ACGACUUGUCCCGCCGCCACCCGCGCCGCGGCCGCCCAACAGGGACGCGAGCCGGGACCACGCCGACCCAGCGUGCCCAGGCCGAGGAAAGCGCGGCGGCGGCAGUCCGAAGACCCACCGGGACUGAAAGAGAAGGACGAGGUCAUCUUCGGACGGGAGGGGCAAGCCAGCCAUCCUGGGACCCCAGGCGUGCAGGUUCUCUUUGAGGGUAUUCCACCCUGCAAAAAGCAUGUAUUCAUGGUCAGCUCUCAGCAAGGCCAGUAGCAGAGUGGUAAAGGCCUUGGCCCUCCAAGGCUGGGAAAAGACAAUGACAAGUCAAAUCCAGACCUAUGUUGUAUGUUGGUCUACUAGGUGACUGUCUCCUGGAAAUGUUAUGCAGCUCAGCAAGGUGAAGUUUCGAAAUCAGUAUGACAAUGAUGUCACUGUUUGGAGCCCCCAGGGCAGGAUUCAUCAAAUUGAAUAUGCAAUGGAAGCUGUUAAACAAGGUUCAGCCACAGUUGGUCUGAAAUCAAAAACUCAUGCAGUUUUGGUUGCAUUGAAAAGGGCGCAAUCAGAGCUUGCAGCUCAUCAGAAAAAAAUUCUCCAUGUUGACAACCAUAUUGGUAUCUCAAUUGCGGGGCUUACUGCUGAUGCUAGACUGUUAUGUAAUUUUAUGCGUCAGGAGUGUUUGGAUUCCAGAUUUGUAUUCGAUAGACCACUGCCUGUGUCUCGUCUUGUAUCUCUAAUUGGAAGCAAGACCCAGAUACCAACACAACGAUAUGGCCGGAGACCAUAUGGUGUUGGUCUCCUUAUUGCUGGUUAUGAUGAUAUGGGCCCUCACAUUUUCCAAACCUGUCCAUCUGCUAACUAUUUUGACUGCAGAGCCAUGUCCAUUGGAGCCCGUUCCCAAUCAGCUCGUACUUACUUGGAGAGACAUAUGUCUGAAUUUAUGGAGUGUAAUUUAAAUGAACUAGUUAAACAUGGUCUGCGUGCCUUAAGAGAGACGCUUCCUGCAGAACAGGACCUGACUACAAAGAAUGUUUCCAUUGGAAUUGUUGGUAAAGACUUGGAGUUUACAAUCUAUGAUGAUGAUGAUGUGUCUCCAUUCCUGGAAGGUCUUGAAGAAAGACCACAGAGAAAGGCACAGCCUGCUCAACCUGCUGAUGAACCUGCAGAAAAGGCUGAUGAACCAAUGGAACAUUAAGUGAUAAGCCAGUCUAUAUAUGUAUUAUCAAAUAUGUAAGAAUACAGGCACCACAUACUGAUGACAAUAAUCUAUACUUUGAACCAAAAGUUGCAGAGUGGUGGAAUGCUAUGUUUUAGGAAUCAGUCCAGAUGUGAGUUUUUUCCAAGCAACCUCACUGAAACCUAUAUAAUGGAAUACAUUUUUCUUUGAAAGGGUCUGUAUAAUCAUUUUCUAGAAAGUAUGGGUAUCUAUACUAAUGUUUUUAUAUGAAGAACAUAGGUGUCUUUGUGGUUUUAAAGACAACUGUGAAAUAAAAUUGUUUCACCGCCUGGUA